CAAAAGAAAGAGGUAAGCGUGGCCUGACCUAGCCACCCACCAACAGGAAUAAUGGCUGAAAAAGCGGGGUCUACAUUUUCACACCUUCUGGUUCCUAUUCUUCUCCUGAUUGGCUGGAUUGUGGGCUGCAUCAUAAUGAUUUAUGUUGUCUUCUCUUAGAAAGGCAAGAAGAUAUCAGAUUGACAUCAUUUAGAAGAAUUAAGAAAACUAUGAACAUGACUGAUUAUUAAAUGUCUCAUGUUAAACAAUGCAAUGUUUGACAUCACUUUACAAACUUGGAUCAUAAACUGGCACUUUGGUAUGCAUAAGAAUUUCUUCAGGACAAUAAGAAAUUAUGAGUGAAUUUCUCUAUAUUCUGAGUGAGAAAAAUGUUUAGCUGUGAUGAAAAAUGCAUGUCAUUAAAAAAAGUUUGAUAAAUUUAAUCACAUUACAAAAAAUUAUCCCCCCUUCCCUCUGGAAAAAACUAUAGAGAAAGUGGGCUGAGGCUGUGCAAGGUGGCUCAUGCCUGUAAUCCCAGCACUUUGUGAGGAUCCUUUGAGCCCAGAAAUUGGAGACCUUCCUAGGCGACAGAGAGAGACCCCAUCUCUACAAAAAAAAAAAAAAAAAAAAAAAAAAAGAAAGAAAAUGGGCUAGAGAUAAAAACAGACAAUUCAGAGAACAUAUAAUGUAAAAGUACACUUACUUAAUCUCUUGUUCACAAAAAGAGAAAUGUAAUUAAAACUACACUGAGGAAUUGUUGCUCACUUAUCAGAUGGGAAAAAAAUAAAGAUGUUUGACAACAUA